GUAGGGACCGACGGCCGGCCAGCUAAUGCUUCCGUCUUGGCCACCUUGCGAGCGCUCGGGUUGAGUUUCCCGGGCUUCCCUGACUCGGCUACCUGUUCUGGAGGUCAGGCUUUGGGCCCUUGCAGAGGUCGCCGAGGGGCCCGCGCCGCCGCCAGAGCCUGGGCCCAGUCCCCAGUCUUCAGAGACGCCCUCGACCUUCCUGCUCCGAGGAGCUGGCCUGAUGUCCUCGGGUCGCGCUCCGCAGGUUCUUACUUUUUCAAACCUAGAGGGCAGUGCAUGAAGCCAGGGGUCAUCAGCCAUGCUCCAGACAGUGUGGUUCCAGGGCUUGGGCAGGAACCUGUUGUUUCAGGAGCCAGUAACCUUUGAGGAUGUGGCUGUGUACUUCACCCAGAAUGAAUGGGCCAGCCUGCACCCUACGCAGAGGGCCCUAUACAGGGAGGUGAUGCUGGAGAAUUAUGCAAAUGUGACUUCCUUGUGACUUUUCUCUUCCCUGGUUCCUAAUGGAGACCCAACUGCAGGGGGCUUUCCUCUGGAUACAGAGAGAACUGAGAAGGUUCCUGGUGCACUGUCUUCAUUCCUUCCAUCUUCCAGUUCCCUGGAGCUGAUCUUGGCCCUAUUGCCUAUGUCAGCAUUUCCAUUCCCCAAACCAGAUCUGAUAUUCCAGCUGGAGCAAGGAGAAGCAGCAUGGGGCCCAGAUCCCUGGACACUUGCUGGGGGAGAGGCCCUGAGAGGCAUGUGCACAGGUGGUAAAACCAAGACUGAGAAUGAGGAAAAAACUGCACAGCUAAACAUUUCUAAAGAAUCAGAGUCCCACAGACUGAUAGUGGAGGGACUGCUGAUGGACGUUCCCCAGCACCCUGACUUCAAGGACAGGUUAGAGAAGUCACAGCUACAUGAUACAGGGAAUAAAACAAAGAUAGGGGAUUGCACAGAUUUGACAGUCCAGGAUCAUGAAUCUUCCACCACUGAAAGGGAGGAGAUAGCCAGGAAAUUGGAAGAAAGUAGUGUCAGCACACAUCUCAUUACAAAGCAGGGUUUUGCCAAAGAACAGGUGUUUUAUAAAUGUGGUGAGUGUGGCAGUUACUACAACCCACAUUCAGACUUUCACCUGCAUCAGAGAGUUCACACUAAUGAGAAGCCCUACACAUGCAAAGAAUGUGGGAAAACCUUCAGAUAUAACUCAAAACUGUCACGGCAUCAGAAAAUCCACACUGGAGAGAAACCAUACUCAUGUGAGGAAUGUGGACAAGCCUUCAGUCAAAAUUCCCACCUUCUUCAGCAUCAGAAGCUCCAUGGUGGACAGAGGCCCUAUGAAUGUACUGACUGUGGUAAAACCUUCAGUUAUAAUUCAAAACUGAUUCGGCAUCAGAGAAUCCAUACUGGGGAGAAGCCCUUUAAAUGUAAGGAAUGUGGGAAAGCCUUCAGUUGUAGCUAUGACUGCAUCAUCCAUGAACGAAUUCACAAUGGGGAGAAGCCCUAUGAAUGUAAGGAGUGUGGGAAGAGUUUGAGUUCUAAUUCAGUUCUGAUUCAGCAUCAGAGAAUCCACACUGGGGAGAAACCUUAUGAAUGUAAAGAGUGUGGCAAGGCCUUCCACCGCAGUUCGGUAUUUCUUCAGCACCAGAGGUUCCACACUGGGGAACAACUCUACAAAUGUAAUGAAUGUUGGAAAACUUUCAGCUGUAGCUCCCGCUUCAUAGUGCAUCAGAGAAUCCACAAUGGGGAGAAACCCUAUGAAUGCCAGGAAUGUGGGAAGACAUUCAGUCAAAAGAUCACUCUGGUUCAGCAUCAGCGAGUUCACACUGGGGAGAAACCUUAUGAGUGUAAGGAGUGCGGGAAAGCCUUCAGAUGGAAUGCAAGUUUCAUCCAGCAUCAGAAGUGGCAUACUAGGAAGAAACUCAUCAAUGGAACAGGGCUAUCCGCAGUUAAGCCCUACUGUCCCUGCGCCAUCCUCUCUCCUCUGCCUCCCCAACAUACCUGCUCUGCCCUAGCCCCACCAGGGCCUCCCUUAUCUUCUUCACAUGCAGUGGUACUUCCUCCCUCUGUGCCUUUCUUCCUGCUGCUUCCCUCAUCUGAAAAGGCCAACCCUUCACCUGUCCAAAUAGCACAUUUUUUUCAGGAUCUCGCUUUUCCUGGGAAGUCAUCCCUUCAGAGCCCGAAUCCUUUGUCUCACUCCCUGUAAGCCCCGUCACGUUCUCAAAAUCCUUUGCACCUCAAGUUAGGGAUUCCACUGGUCUCCUGAUUGUGUCUAUUGAUAUUCCUCUGGUCUUGUCUUGUAUAAGUUGUUACUGUUUUCCUAACUUCAUUUUAAAUUCUCACGCUUAAGGACCAUGUUUGAUUAGUUUCUUUUAUCCCCCGGUAGGAAAUGGCAGUACUUAUUCUUUAUCGUGUCCACAUUUGGGCUGUAUUAUCAGUCUGCAUCUCUCUUCUGGGGCUACUGGAGUUGGAAGAGUUUGCAGAACAUUUUGGGGUUUAGGGCAUAUGGCAUUAUGAUUAUGAUGAGAUGGGGCAUUAUAAUUAGAGACUAGGAGAAAUGCAAAGCCUAUGGGAGAACAUAAUCAGAUAAAGUGUCCAAUGAUUGCUUUCAAGAGCUUUUUUUUUUUUAGGGGGUGGGGGGUGGUGCCGGAGUUUCACUCUUGUCACCCAGGCUGUUUGCAGUGGUGUGAUCUUGGCUCACUGCAACCUCUGCCUCCAGGGUUCAAGUGAUUCUCAUGCCUCAGCCUCCCGAGUAGCUGGGACCACAGGCAUGCACCACCACGCCCCGCUAAUUUUGUAUUUUUAGUAGAGACAGGGUUUCACCAUGUUGGCCAGGCUGGUCUCAAAAUCCUGACCUCAGGUGAUUCACCUGCCUCAGUCUCCCAAGUGCUGGGAUUACAGGCAUGAGCCACUGCAUCUGGCCUGCUUUCAGGAGUUAAGGAGGGCCAUUUGGUGGACCAGGGGCAAGGCUCACUGAAAGAAUGUAAGACUUGGAAUUUUUUAUUACCUUGAUAGUAUAAAAAAUUAUGAGGGUCCUUUUAUGCAAAAAGAAAAUGAAGUGAUGAGUUGGCAUUGAUAGCAAUAAUGUAAAAUUAUGUCUUUGAGCUUUAUUGGAAGGGGAUAUGGUUUUUCAAUUUGGGUUCCUUCUCUAUUUUCAUUUUCCUUUUUUUUUUGAGACAGGUUCUUGUUCUGUCAUCCAGGCUGGAUUGCAGUAGUGCGAUCAUGGAUCACUGCAGUGUGUUGACCUUCCAGGCUCAAGCAAUCCUCCCACCUCAGCUUCCCAAGAAGCUGGGAGGUAGUGCAGCCUCCCAGUUUCUCAGAGGGCUGAGGUGGGAGGAUUGCUUGAGCCCUGGGGGCAUACACCACCACACCCAGCUAAUUUUUGUAUUUUUUGUAGAGACAGAGUUUUGCCAUGUUGCCCAGGCUGGUCUCAAAACUCCUGGACUCAAAUGAUCCUCCCACUUCAGCCUCCCAAAGUGCUGGGAUUACAGGCUUGAGCCACCAUGUCCAGCCUCUAUUCCUUUUCAUAUCUGUUGAAUUUCAGUACCCACUCAUAUAUGUAGGUACAAAAAGUGACUUGGACUUGUACCCUUUAGGGUAGAUGCCUGAGUAUAGUAAUCUCUAAAGCUGUACAUGGAUGGAACUUGUUGGCAUCACACUGGUGAGCACCAGAGGCAAAGAAGAGAAACCUGACCAUGACUUGCUGUAGUUUCUCAGAAGUGAGUCCAUUCCUGAUGAGUUACUAUGCAGGCCCUUGGAUAUGUCCUCACACCUACUCCAGAUUUCCCUAUGAUUAAAUCUGAAUUUUAUUGGUGGCACUUUUAAAUUAGUUUUAUAAAGAACUGUUUUGAUGACACCAAGAAAUGUUUUCAGUGUGCAGAUUGCUAUUGUUUGAAUAUCCCCAGCAAAAUUCUUGUUGAAACUUAAUCCCCAUUGUAACAGUACUGGGUGGGGGGUCUUUAAGAGGUGAUCAGGAUUAGCCAAGUUCAUCAGGGUGGAGCCUCCAUGAUGGGACUGGUGGCUUUAUGAGGAGAGGAAGAGCAACUGGAACUGGGACACAUGCUUGCUCUGUCUUGCCUUUUGAUGCCUCCUGCCAUGUCAUGAUGCAGCAAGUAAGCCCUUACCAGAUGCCUGCACCUUUAUAUUGGACUUCUUAGCCUUCAGAACUGUGAACUAAAUAAACCUCUAUUCUGUAUAAAUUACCCAGUCUAUGGUAUUCAGUUAGAGCCACACAAAAUGUAACAAGACAGAAUAUUGAUAGCCAUAAGUAGGUUUGCUGCUCUGACAUUUACAUAAAAAUGUAGAAGUGGCUUUGGAACUGAGUAAUGGGUAGAGGCUUGAAAAAUCUGGAAGAUCAGGUCAGACAAAGCCUGUAUUAUCUAAUGGAGCAUUAAGGGUGAUUUUGGCCAAGGCUUAGAAGAGAAGACUAGGGAAAGUCUGAACCUUCUUAGAGAUUACAGGAGGUCCUUGAACAACUUGGGUUUCAACUGUGUGGGUCCACUUAUGGACUUUCUUCUGCCUCUGUCACCCCUGAGAUGGCAAGACCAGUCUCCCUCCUCUCCCCUUCUCAGCCUGCUUAACAAAAUGACAAGGAUACAGACCUUUAUGAUGAUCCAUAUAAUAUAGUGAAUUAUAUUUACUAAAUAUAAUUUCUCUUAUGAUUUUCUUAAUAUUUUCUCUAGCUUUAUUAUAAGAAUAUAGUGUCUAAUAUGUAUAACAUAAAAAAUAUGUGUUAAUCGACUGUUUCAGUAAGGCUCUGGUCAACAGUAGACUAUUAGUAGUUACAUUUUUGGGGAGUUAAAAGUUAUACAUGGCAUGGGGGUUGGUGCCCAUAUGAUGGGACUGAUGGCUUUAUAAGAAGAGGAAGGGAGACCUGAGCUGACAUGCAUGCUCUUGCCAUCUUGCCAUGUGAUGCUUUCCAUCAUGUUAUGACACAGCAAGAAGGCCAGAUACGGCCCCUCCACAGUUCCCAGCCCUCGGAACCAUGAGCUAAAUAAACUUCUUUUCUUUAUAAAUUA